CUCUCGCCAGCUGGGAGUCGCGCGCUGCCCACCUCGCUGCCCAGGCCCCCGACGCCGCGGCAGGAGCCCCCCAAGAGCGCGGGAAGCCCCGUGGACCUGGCGCUCCCGGCUCGGGCGUGGACGGGGCGGGCGCCGGGGCGGGGCGCGCGUCCUCGCGGGUCUGAAUGGAAGGGUCGAGGUCGUCGUCGGCGGCGAGCAGAUCCUGAAGCCAGAACUCCACCCCGGCGCCCGCGCCAUGCGGCGGGAGAGGUGAGCGCGGCGGGCGUGGCGUCCGUGCCGGGGUGCCCGGGGUGCCACGGGAACGGCGAGGCCGGGGACACGCGCGCAGGACGCCAGCGGCGGAGGUGCGGCGCCCCCCACCCGCGUCGCCGCCAUGGAGGUGCUGCGGCGCUCCUCGGUCUUCGCCGCCGAGAUCAUGGACGCCUUUGACCGCUCGCCCACAGACAAGGAGCUGGUGGCCCAGGCCAAGGCGCUGGGCCGGGAGUACGUGCACGCGCGGCUGCUGCGCGCCGGCCUCUCCUGGAGCGCGCCCGAGCGUGCCGCGCCGGUCCCGGGACGCCUGGCUGAGGUGUGCGCGGUGCUGCUGCGCCUGGGCGAUGAGCUGGAGAUGAUCCGGCCCAGCGUCUACCGCAACGUGGCGCGUCAGCUGCACAUCUCCCUGCAGUCUGAGCCUGUGGUGACCGAUGCGUUCCUGGCCGUGGCUGGCCACAUCUUCUCUGCAGGCAUCACGUGGGGCAAGGUGGUGUCCCUGUAUGCGGUGGCCGCGGGGCUGGCCGUGGACUGUGUGAGGCAGGCCCAGCCUGCCAUGGUCCACGCCCUCGUGGACUGCCUGGGGGAGUUCGUGCGCAAGACCCUGGCAACCUGGCUGCGGAGACGCGGCGGAUGGACUGAUGUCCUCAAGUGUGUGGUCAGCACAGACCCUGGCCUCCGCUCCCACUGGCUGGUGGCUGCACUCUGCAGCUUCGGCCGCUUCCUGAAGGCUGCCUUCUUCGUGCUGCUGCCAGAGAGAUGAGCUGCCCACCUGGCAGUGGCCGCAGCCUGGCCCUCUGGGCCCAACGCAGGAGGCCCUCAGCACCCGAACACAUCUUCCUCCUCCCCACCCGAGCCUGGAGCACUCUAACCCUCGGAGACCCCCUAAGCCCCGUUCCUCCGCAGACCCAGGCCCUCCGGAAGGGGUGAGUGGGGAGGGGCUUUCCUGAGCCUGGAGCUGGGCUUUGGGGCAGCCUGCGACCCUCCCCGCUUGUGUCCCUUCUCCUGUGAUCUCUGUGUUUUCCCUUUUCUUUCUGGGGCCAGGAAGUCAGGGUCAACUCCCAGGCCUCAGAUGCAGGGGCCCAGAACACCUGCUCUCACCUGAGCCCCAGGUGAAGGGGCCCGGGAACACCUGCUCUCACCUGAGCCCCAGGUGAAGGGGCCCGGGAACACCUGCUCUCACCUGAACCCCAGGUGAAGGGGCCCGGAACACCUGCUCUCACCUGAGCCCCAGGUGAAGGGGCCCGGAACACCUGCUCUCACCUGAGCCCCAGGUGAAGGGGCCCGGGAACACCUGCUCUCACCUGAGCCCCAGGUGAAGGGGCCCGGGAACACCUGCUCUCACCUGAACCCCAGGUGAAGGGGCCCAGAACACCUGCUCUCACCUGAGCCCCAGGUGAAGGGGCCCGGAACACCUGCUCUCACCUGAGCCCCAGGUGAAGGGGCCCGGGAACACCUGCUCUCACCUGAGCCCCUGGUGAAGGGGCCCGGAACACUUGCUCUCACCUGAGCCCCAGGUGAAGGGGCCCGGAACACCUGCUCUCACCUGAGCCCCCGGUGAAGGGGCCCGGAACACUUGCUCUCACCUGAGCCCCAGGUGAAGGGGCCCGGAACACCUCCUCUCACCUGAGCCCCAGGUGAAGGGGCCCGGAACACCUCCUGUCACCUGAGCCCCAGGUGAAGGGGCCCGGGAACACCUCUCACCUGAACCCGGGGGUCCCAUCCCAGGAAGAAGGGCCAUCUCAGGACAUGAGUCCUCAGGGGCCCUGCACAUUCAAUCUGAAGGUGACCCUGGCCUGGCUGAAGCUGGAAGAGCUGUGGGGACUCAGCCUGUAAACAGAGCGUAAGGUUCACAUGCUGGUUGCUUAAUCCGUUUCUGGAGGAAGAGUAUGACACCCACUUGUGAUGGGGUCCUUGUGCGGUGGGGACCGGGGCCGGCGGGCUCCAGGCCAGCACACCUAACCCAUGGAUGUGGAACCUACGGCCGAGAAGGAAUGUUGCAUGAGUCGGAUCCCAGUCCAUUGUCAGUGGAGGGUGAGGGUGACCCCAUCUGCUAUUUUUGUGCUCAUCCUCAUACAACCAUUUGGGGAUGUGCCUAUUAGGGCUCCGUAAGAACUCAGAUGCCUGGGAAGCCCAGCCCCUCAGGUGCCCCCACACACAGCCUUCCCUUGACGCCUACAUUUCUAGGCACAUGUGAGGCAUCUUUCCUGGAGCCCCGAGCCAGCCCUGUCCCUCCCCAGUGCAGCAUGGCACUCAGGAGAUACAGGCUGGACAUGGGGCAGUCGUUCUGGGGAGGCCUGGCCUAGCAGCCACCCACCUGAGCCCUCCCGGCCAGGCUUCGUGCUGGGGUGGGCCAUGUGCCAGGACAGGAGGGUCCCGGCGGAAAGCCAGCCCCGGACUCAUCGUGACAUUGAGAUCCCACUGGAGGGUAGGGGUGGUAAUAAACUUCUCCAAACGAUCGUUGUCAUUUUA